CUCCUCUUCUCCUGGCAGGUGGUACCCAGGCAGAAUUCUGCCUUCAGUCUCUCUCUCGCUCCGCUCCCGGCCGUGAGGCGCUCGCCGCUGCUCGCUCGCUCCUCCGCCCCAGCUCUGAGCCUCGCCGUGCCGACCGUGCCCGCCGCCGCCGCCGCUGGGCGCACCCGGGGGACGCCCGGGCCCACGCGGGGCUUUGGGGUGCGCGUCUAUUCGAGUUGUGGUGGUGGCAAAGGAGGAAGAGAGAAAGGAGGCAAUAAAAAAAAAAGGCAGCGGACGGGCGAACUGAGCGAGCGAAAGAAGAGGAGGAGGAGGCAGAAAAAGGCAACUUCAGACGGAAAGUUGGUGCGAACAGGCGCAGUCUGCAAAAACGGAAAAGUCGAUCGCAGGCGGCGGCGGCAUAAAAGUGUGAGCUGCCCGGGCGAGCUCAGGAGGCGGCGGCUGGCUCUGCCCUCCCGGUGGCCGCGCCGGCGCCGGCUGCAGCCACAGGUGCGAAGGAGCUCGCGGGGGGCGAGGGCGCCCCGCGCACCCCUCCCCCGGCCCCCACCCCGGGCUCGGGACUUCGGCUCAAGUCACUGGGCGCCCGCGCUCCCUCCCCAGCCGCAGCCUCCGCGGGGGGAGCAGGAGUCGGCAGCAGCGGCCGGCGCACGCACGCCCAGGGGAGUUGGGGUUCGCAGGGGGUUGUUUUCGGCUCUGAAGAGGUCCCCGCCCAACCUUCAAAAUUCUGUCCAAAAGCAGACAAGAGGAUCGCCCCGCGCUGAGCCGGCUGGUGGGCAGCAGGAGGCGCCUGAUCGCCGCCGGGGCGCUGGGGGUGGUGAUGGUGCUGCUGCUGGUGAUCCUCAUCCCGGUGCUGGUGAGCUCGGCCGGCACGUCGGCGCACUACGAGAUGCUGGGCACCUGCCGCAUGGUCUGCGACCCCUACGGGGGCACCAAGGCGCCCAGCACCGCUGCCACGCCCGACCGCGGCCUCAUGCAGUCCCUGCCCACCUUCAUCCAGGGCCCCAAAGGCGAGGCCGGCAGGCCCGGGAAGGCGGGUCCGCGCGGGCCCCCCGGAGAGCCCGGGCCACCCGGCCCCAUGGGGCCCCCGGGCGAGAAGGGCGAGCCGGGCCGCCAAGGCCUGCCGGGCCCGCCCGGGGCGCCCGGCCUGAACGCGGCCGGGGCCAUCAGCGCCGCCACCUACAGCACGGUGCCCAAGAUCGCCUUCUACGCCGGCCUCAAGCGGCAGCAUGAAGGCUACGAGGUGCUCAAGUUCGACGACGUGGUCACCAACCUCGGAAACCACUACGACCCCACCACCGGCAAGUUCACCUGCUCCAUCCCGGGCAUCUACUUCUUCACCUACCACGUCCUGAUGCGCGGAGGGGACGGCACCAGCAUGUGGGCUGAUCUCUGCAAAAACAACCAGGUGCGUGCUAGUGCAAUUGCCCAAGAUGCUGAUCAGAAUUACGACUAUGCCAGUAACAGUGUGGUUCUUCAUUUGGAGCCGGGAGAUGAAGUCUAUAUCAAAUUAGAUGGCGGGAAAGCCCAUGGAGGAAACAACAACAAAUACAGCACGUUUUCUGGAUUUAUUAUUUAUGCUGACUGAUAAUGCAGAAACUAAGCUUAUUAUUCUGAGUUUGAACACUGGAUUCGUAUGGCUAACGUCAGUGAAUCAAGGAUCCCAGGGGAUGCCAAUGGCAGGGCACCUCAGUUGUGUAUAUGUGGGGAAAUCAAAUGCUACCUGACUCACAUCUGUAUCACUCAGAAACAUUAUGUAAAAAAUAUCAAAGCAAGAUAAGCAGAUGUGUGAUCCACUACCGCCAAAGCAAAUACUCCUUAUCGUUAGUGUCCAUGUGAAUGAAGUCCUAUAUAGAUCACAAAUUUUUAUAGACAAAUCUAAGACAUUGAAUUAUUUCUUCUAUAUAUAUGAUACUUUGGUGUACUGUGAUCUUGCUGCUUUUAUCCAUAUGUCAGCUUUGGUUCUUGUGAGUUUACCUGCUUAUUAUGAUACUUGGAGUCCAUUCAUAGUGUGGGGAAGAAUGAUUUUUGCCCUGCAGGAGAAGGUCUAAUUGAAAUAAUGCUGCUUGUCCCCAAAGAAAUUGUUUGCCUUGUACUCUUGUUAACCUUAGAGCUAGACCUGGGAAUGAUUCAACUUCAAGCCUUAACCUGGAAUUUUCUGGAUUUGAGGGAAUUCCCAAGCCUAUGAUCUUUUUCACAUUUUCUUUUUCUUAUAUGAAUUUUCUUUUCUCUCUUUUCUGGUGAUAGUCUUUAAAAAUAGAGAUUGACAGUGUAUCAUAGGAUUACCCUCUAAGUGUGAAAAUGUGUAAUUAUGUACGGUAUUUAGAAAAAGCCCUUAUGUGUCCAUUUUGUCAACUGAAUACAUUUAGAUUCACUGGGAAA